GGGACAUGAGGAAAGGAACAAGGGAAAGAGCCGGUGAAGGGGCAGAACAGGCAGGUGAGAGUCUAAGAGGGCUCAGUAAUCUGAAGCUUGGUGGGAAGAAGGGAUUCUGGGCUAGAAAGGGUGCAGAAGCCUGAAGUAGAAAGAGACGGGAUUUUGGUCCGGGGUGGAGAGCGAAUGCAUUGAAAAGGGCCAAGGCCCAGGAUAAGGUAGACAUUUAAAGGGGUACGGAUGCCCAAGGUAGAGCAGACACUUGAGGAGACCAGCUCAGCAAACGGAAGACACUUAAAGUGGUAGGUUCUCAAGAGAGAAGAAGUUUUUAAGACUAGAGCUAAGCAAGACAUUUAAAAGGACAUGGGUUGGGAUUUGGGAACACGUUUAUUCCAGAGGCAGGAACAAAGGAGUCGCUUGUCAAGGAUCUGGUUAGAGAAGACUAGGGUCUUCCUCGAAGGAAGCACGCGCACGCCUGCUCUCCCCCAUUGUCUUUUCUGGCUUCUCCAGGUUCCCUCGACCCAGGACCCCCUGUUCCCAGGCUAUGGCCCCCAGUGCCCUGUAGACCUGGCAGGCCCCCCGUGCUUGCGACCCCUAUUUGGGGGUCUGGGUGGCUACUGGAGGGCCUUGCAGAGGGGCAGAGAAGGCAGGACCAUGACAUCUAGGGCCUCUGAACUUUCUCCGGGGCGCAGCGUGACGGCUGGCAUCAUCAUUGUUGGAGAUGAGAUCCUUAAGGGACACACUCAGGACACCAACACCUUCUUUCUGUGCCGGACACUGCGCUCCCUAGGGGUCCAGGUUUGCCGAGUCUCAGUUGUACCUGAUGAGGUAGCCACCAUUGCAGCUGAGGUCACUUCUUUCUCCAACCGCUUCACCCAUGUCCUCACAGCAGGGGGCAUCGGCCCCACUCAUGAUGAUGUGACCUUUGAGGCAGUGGCACAGGCCUUUGGAGAUGAGCUGAAGCCACACCCCAAGUUGGAAGCAGCCACCAAAGCCCUAGGAGGGGAAGGCUGGGAGAAGCUAUCAUUGGUGCCCUCCUCUGCCCGCCUGCAUUAUGGCACAGAUCCUUGCACUGGUCAACCUUUCAGAUUCCCUCUGGUCUCCGUCCGAAACGUCUACCUCUUCCCAGGCAUUCCAGAGCUGCUGCGGCGGGUGCUGGAGGGGAUGAAGGGACUAUUCCAAAACCCAGCUGUUCAGUUCCACUCAAAGGAGCUAUAUGUGGCUGCUGAUGAAGCCUCCAUCGCCCCCAUUCUGGCUGAGGCCCAGGCCCACUUUGGACGUAGGCUUGGCCUGGGUUCCUACCCUGACUGGGGCAGCAACUACUAUCAGGUGAAGCUGACUCUAGACUCAGAGGAAGAAGGACCCCUGGAGGAAUGCUUGGCCUACCUGACUGCCCGUUUGCCCCAGGGAUCGCUGGUCCCCUACAUGCCCAACGCUGUGGAGCAGGCCAGUGAGGCUGUAUACAAACUCGCUGAAUCAGGGUCUUCUUUGGGGAAAAAGGUGGCAGGUGCCCUACAGACCAUUGAGACCUCCCUGGCUCAGUACAGCCUCACCCAGCUCUGUGUGGGCUUCAACGGGGGCAAAGACUGCACUGCCCUCCUGCACCUCUUCCAUGCAGCUGUGCAGAGGAAAUUACCUGAUGUUCCAAACCCCCUCCAGAUCCUGUAUAUCCGCAGCAUCUCCCCUUUCCCUGAGCUGGAACAGUUUCUACAGGACACUAUCAAGAGGUAUAAUCUGCAGAUGUUGGAAGCUGAGGGCAGCAUGAAGCAGGCCCUGGGUGAACUGCAGGCACGGCACCCCCAGCUGGAGGCUGUCCUUAUGGGCACCCGCCGGACUGACCCCUACUCCUGUAGCCUCUGCCCUUUCAGCCCCACUGACCCAGGCUGGCCCGCAUUCAUGCGCAUCAACCCACUGCUGGACUGGACCUACAGAGACAUCUGGGAUUUUCUGCGUCAGCUGUUUGUCCCAUACUGUAUCCUGUAUGACCGAGGAUACACAUCACUGGGGAGUCGGGAGAAUACCGUGCGGAACCCGGCCCUGAAGUGCCUGAGCCCAGGAGGACACCCCACAUACCGUCCAGCCUAUCUACUGGAGAACGAAGAAGAGGAGCGGAACUCCCGCACAUGACCUCCCACCCUAGGAGGGAGGGAAGGACACCGUCCUAGGGUAUAACCUGGCAAUAAACCGUGCCUCUCACUGUG